CUCUCUUCAUUUAAGCACGACUCUGCAGAAGGAACAAAGCACCCUCCCCACUGGGCUCCUGGUUGCAGAGCUCCAAGUCCUCACACAGAUACGCCUGUUUGAGAAGCAGCGGGCAAGAAAGACGCAAGCCCAGAGGCCCUGCCAUUUCUGUGGGCUCAGGUCCCUACUGGCUCAGGCCCCUGCCUCCCUCGGCAAGGCCACAAUGAACCGGGGAGUCCCUUUUAGGCACUUGCUUCUGGUGCUGCAACUGGCGCUCCUCCCAGCAGCCACUCAGGGAAAGAAAGUGGUGCUGGGCAAAAAAGGGGAUACAGUGGAACUGACCUGUACAGCUUCCCAGAAGAAGAGCAUACAAUUCCACUGGAAAAACUCCAACCAGAUAAAGAUUCUGGGAAAUCAGGGCUCCUUCUUAACUAAAGGUCCAUCCAAGCUGAAUGAUCGCGCUGACUCAAGAAGAAGCCUUUGGGACCAAGGAAACUUUCCCCUGAUCAUCAAGAAUCUUAAGAUAGAAGACUCAGAUACUUACAUCUGUGAAGUGGAGGACCAGAAGGAGGAGGUGCAAUUGCUAGUGUUCGGAUGUGAGUGGGGCAGGUGGGGAUGAGGAUACCUCCUGCCUGGUUCCCUUCCCCACUACUCCCACCCCUGCACCAAAUCCAGCCUGAGCUGGUGAUACCGCAGCAGCCCCAAGAGGACCAGGCUGUCAAACUGGCCUCCAAAUGUCUUAAAACCCUUCUUGAUCAGUGACUGCCAACUCUGACACCCACCUGCUUCAGGGGCAGAGCCUGACCCUGACCUUGGAGAGCCCCCCUGGUAGUAGCCCCUCAGUGCAAUGUAGGAGUCCAAGGGGUAAAAACAUACAGGGGGGGAAGACCCUCUCCGUGUCUCAGCUGGAGCUCCAGGAUAGUGGCACCUGGACAUGCACUGUCUUGCAGAACCAGAAGAAGGUGGAGUUCAAAAUAGACAUCGUGGUGCUAGCUUUCCAGAAGGCCUCCAGCAUAGUCUAUAAGAAAGAGGGGGAACAGGUGGAGUUCUCCUUCCCACUCGCCUUUACAGUUGAAAAGCUGACGGGCAGUGGCGAGCUGUGGUGGCAGGCGGAGAGGGCUUCCUCCUCCAAGUCUUGGAUCACCUUUGACCUGAAGAACAAGGAAGUGUCUGUAAAACGGGUUACCCAGGACCCUAAGCUCCAGAUGGGCAAGAAGCUCCCGCUCCACCUCACCCUGCCCCAGGCCUUGCCUCAGUAUGCUGGCUCUGGAAACCUCACCCUGGCCCUUGAAGCGAAAACAGGAAAGUUGCAUCAGGAAGUGAACCUGGUGGUGAUGAGAGCCACUCAGCUCCAGAAAAAUUUGACCUGUGAGGUGUGGGGACCCACCUCCCCUAAGCUGAUGCUGAGUUUGAAACUGGAGAACAAGGAGGCAAAGGUCUCGAAGCGGGAGAAGGCGGUGUGGGUGCUGAACCCUGAGGCGGGGAUGUGGCAGUGUCUGCUGAGUGACUCGGGACAGGUCCUGCUGGAAUCCAACAUCAAGGUUCUGCCCACAUGGUCCACCCCGGUGCAGCCAAUGGCCCUGAUUGUGCUGGGGGGCGUCGCCGGCCUCCUGCUUUUCAUUGGGCUAGGCAUCUUCUUCUGUGUCAGGUGCCGGCACCGAAGGCGCCAAGCAGAGCGGAUGUCUCAGAUCAAGAGACUCCUCAGUGAGAAGAAGACCUGCCAGUGUCCUCACCGGUUUCAGAAGACAUGUAGCCCCAUUUGAGGCACGAGGCCAGGCAGAUCCCACUUGCAGCCUCCCCAGGUGUCUGCCCCGCGUUUCCUGCCUGCGGACCAGAUGAAUGUAGCAGAUCCCCAGCCUCUGGCCUCCUGUUCGCCUCCUCUACAAUUUGCCAUUGUUUCUCCUGGGUUAGGCCCCGGCUUCACUGGUUGAGUGUUGCUCUCUAGUUUCCAGAGGCUUAAUCACACCGUCCUCCACGCCAUUUCCUUUUCCUUCAAGCCUAGCCCUUCUCUCAUUAUUUCUCUCUGACCCUCUCCCCACUGCUCAUUUGGAUCCCAGGGGAGUGUUCAGGGCCAGCCCUGGCUGGCAUGGAGGGUGAGGCUGGGUGUCUGGAAGCAUGGAGCAUGGGACUGUUCUUUUACAAGACAGGACCCUGGGACCACAGAGGGCAGGAACUUGCACAAAAUCACACAGCCAAGCCAGUCAAGGAUGGAUGCAGAUCCAGAGGUUUCUGGCAGCCAGUACCUCCUGCCCCAUGCUGCCCGCUUCUCACCCUAUGUGGGUGGGACCACAGACUCACAUCCUGACCUUGCACAAACAGCCCCUCUGGACACAGCCCCAUGUACACGGCCUCAAGGGAUGUCUCACAUCCUCUGUCUAUUUGAGACUUAGAAAAAUCCUACAAGGCUGGCAGUGACAGAACUAAGAUGAUCAUCUCCAGUUUAUAGACCAGAACCAGAGCUCAGAGAGGCUAGAUGAUUGAUUACCAAGUGCCGGACUAGCAAGUGCUGGAGUCGGGACUAACCCAGGUCCCUUGUCCCAAGUUCCACUGCUGCCUCUUGAAUGCAGGGACAAAUGCCACACGGCUCUCACCAGUGGCUAGUGGUGGGUACUCAAUGUGUACUUUUGGGUUCACAGAAGCACAGCACCCAUGGGAAGGGUCCAUCUCAGAGAAUUUACGAGCAGGGAUGAAGGCCUCCCUGUCUAAAAUCCCUCCUUCAUCCCCCGCUGGUGGCAGAAUCUGUUACCAGAGGACAAAGCCUUUGGCUCUUCUAAUCAGAGCGCAAGCUGGGAGCACAGGCACUGCAGGAGAGAAUGCCCAGUGACCAGUCACUGACCCUGUGCAGAACCUCCUGGAAGCGAGCUUUGCUGGGAGAGGGGGUAGCUAGCCUGAGAGGGAACCCUCUAAGGGACCUCAAAGGUGAUUGUGCCAGGCUCUGCGCCUGCCCCACACCCUCCCUUACCCUCCUCCAGACCAUUCAGGACACAGGGAAAUCAGGGUUACAAAUCUUCUUGAUCCACUUCUCUCAGGAUCCCCUCUCUUCCUACCCUUCCUCACCACUUCCCUCAGUCCCAACUCCUUUUCCCUAUUUCCUUCUCCUCCUGUCUUUAAAGCCUGCCUCUUCCAGGAAGACCCCCCUAUUGCUGCUGGGGCUCCCCAUUUGCUUACUUUGCAUUUGUGCCCACUCUCCACCCCUGCUCCCCUGAGCUGAAAUAAAAAUACAAUAAACUUAC